ACCUGUGGGGCAGCGGAGCUGGGCUGAGCCAUAUGGGAAGAAAAUCUGGGCGCUAGUUUAGAUUUGGUCAGGAAGGGUCGUUAAUGCUUUAGGAGGUGAGAUUAGUUUUGGGGAUGGCAGGUAGUUUGUUGAGCUUUUGUUUAGACAGUCUUGCUCUGUUGUCCAGGCUGGAGUGCAAUGGCGCGAUCUCGGCUCACUGCAACCUCCACCUCCCUCGUUCAAGCAAUUCCCCUGCCUCAGCCUCCCUAGUAGCUGGGAUUACAGGCGACACCACCAAGCCUGGCUAAUUUUUUUGUAUUUUUAGUAGAGACGGAGUUUCACCAUAUCGGCCAGGCUAAUCUCAAACUCCUGACCUUGCGAUCCACCUGCCUCAGCCUUCUGCAAUGCUGGGAUUACAGACGUGAGCCACCCCGACCAAUUUUUGUAUUUUUUAGUAGAGACGGGGUUUCACCAUCUUGGAAUAGCACCUGUAGUUCCAGCUACUCGGGAGGCCGAGGCGGAAGAAUUGCUUGAGGCCAGUUCCCGACCAGCCUAGGCAACACAGGGAGACUGCGUUUCUGGAAAAAACAACAACAACACCAGCAACAACAAAAAGCAGGAAGGAAGGGGAGAGGGAAAGAGAAAGAGAGAGAGAGAGAACGAAAGAGAAAGAGAAAAGGAAGGAAGGAAGGAAGGAAAGAAAGAAAAAAAGAAAGAGGGAUACUUUGAGAAGCUUUGAAGUGAUCUGUUUAUUGAUCAAGUAGAUAGGUAAGGUGCAUGCUGCCAGGAGGAGCUGGGGUAGGGAGGGCAGGGCCCUGCUGUAUGGGGGUGGGCAGGGGACGGCCCCUGCUCAGCCCUGGCCUCCAUUGCUACACAGAAUGGCAGGUCCAAUGUGAUCUGGUCUUCUGAUUUUUCAGGAGAAAUCAGGAAUCUGAGGUGCAUGCAAAAUCUCCUGAUUUUUAAAUAUUGGCAACUAAUUUGUUUUAAAAAAACAACAACUAUGAGCUAAUCCAAAACUGUUUGCUGGUGGGAUCCACCUACUGCCUUUGCGCUGGGGUAUGGAGAGGUGGGAGGUCAAUGUUGACAAGAGCCAGAUCUAAUUUUUUGUUAAAGAAAAGGGUACUUGGAGGUCAGAUAGCUCUCUUCAUAGCUAUCUGAAGCCUUCCUCUCCCUUAUCUCUUACAAUCUGGUCCAAACUCAGAAAGCUAGGCCGCUCUCGGUGAGAUGGGCUUGUCUCCGUCUCUCUGUACCUGUCAGAGCAGCCUGGGCGCCUGCAAGAAACCGGGGCUUCCAGUUGGCAUUUGCCUUCCCUGUGGCUGGCAGAUGGGCUUCCUGUGAUCAAGGCCUGGUAUGUGGAUAAAUCUGAGUGUGAAAUAGGUGUGAUACAGUGGGGGAGGGGGAGCCACACUCCCACCCCCUAAGGUCUGUCCCCAUCCUCCCUCCUCACCCACUUCCCUGUCAUUUACAGACAAAGGCAGCCUUGCGGUGGGAGAAGGAGCAGGGUGGGCUUCCCUCUCAAUCUGGUGAGCCUGGAGAAUUCAGGAAGCUGAGCUUUUUAGCAAGGGCUCAGGAGAUGGAGUUACUAACCUUUCUUCCCCAACAAGAGCCUGUUAAUGCUCUAACUUCUGAAAUGAUUACUACAAAGAAAUUGAACCUUGGAUGGAGUCAGCCACAACAUCUCUACCCGUGGUGCUGGACUAUUAAAACACAGUGACUUCCUCUGCCUGCCCUCACACACGCAGUGAUAGCUGCUGGCCCUCCCAUUCUGCAGAACCCUGGGCUUGUGUCUCAGUGAAACCUGCCUCAUUGUCUGAGAUAUCACUGAAGUUCUGGGUCUCAUGGCCAAGGAAAUCAAGGACGCAGACACUCCAGAGGGUAGGUUAGAGCAGAAGUUUAAUAAGCAAAAGAAAGAAAGCUCUCUGGAUCAGAGAGGGGUCCCAGAAAGAUGGGUUGCCAUUUUACAGUGAAAUGCAAGGGUUUUUAUAGAAAAGCUGGUGGGAGGGGUGCUUCAUUUACAUAAGGUGCGAAUUUCUGAGUCCCCCGCCCCACUGUUUCUAGUGCACAUGUGGGCUUCUUAGCCUGAGUUACUACUCCAUGUUGCUUAUUUCUUCCUACUGUGCAUGUGUGAAAAAGGUUGGGUGGUGGGGGGGAAGAACACUCCAAGGUAGACAUGCCUGGUCCAGGGUAGCUCUUCUUAUCAGUGCCAUGCAAGCCUCUGUGUCUGAGUAUUUCUUUUUUCUUUUUUUUUUGAGACGGAGUCCCACUCUGCUGCCAGGCUGGAGUGCAGUGGUGUGAUCUCAGCUCACUGCAACCUCCACCUCCCGGGUUCAAGUGGUUCUCCUGCCUCAGCCUCCCAAGUAGCUGGGAUUACAGGCGAGCACCAUGACACCUGGCUAAUUUUUGUAUUUUUUUAGUAGAGAUGGGUUUUCACCAUGUUGGCCAGGAUAGUCUCGAUCUCUUGACCUCGUGAUCUGCCCACCUCGGCUUCCCAAAGUGCUGGGAUUACAAGCGUGAGCCACCGUGGCCGGCCGUGUCUUGAGUAUUUCUAAGAAGGGAGAGGACUGUGCUUACUGGGGCCCACCAUAUGUCUGUAUGUCACACAGGGGACCCGCUUUCUGUGUUAGAGCUUGCCUUCCUUAUCUGUGUUUCCUGAAAGGGCAACGACUUCUUAGGCUGCUUUUUGUUAGAAGGGAAUUCUGCCAAGGACCCUUGCCCUAACUAUUUGCCUAAUUGAUUUCUCUCUCUCCUCUCACAUUGAUGCUGGCCUGGCUGGAGCAGGUAGAGCUGGAAGUAGCAUUUUUGCAAGGACAUCUCUUUAGCCUCUGUAGAUUUUCACCUCAAGUCAUUCGGAGCAGGUCGGAAGCUAGGUUUUUUUUGGGGGGGGAAGCCAGUAGAGCUAAAGUGGUUAUGUAUCUGUUUCCUGCCUUCCUUCUUUCCACUUCUACAUGCAUUUUCUUGCUGUGCAGAAACUGUUUUGAGAGUGCAGACCCAAAACUGCAGAAAACCUGUUUUGGGAGUGGUGUCUGGGUGCUGGCCUGGAAGCCAGCCUUGCAGACCAAGCAUGGCAGGGCUCAGGGUCUUCACGCCCGGGGAAAGGGAGGUUCCUUGCAGCCUCCAAAGGGGCCCUCCUGAGACCUGGGCAGUGCCUCUCUUUUUCCAAUAUAAUUGACAGAUGAAAAGCUGGAUAUAAACCAGAACUAAGCUCAAAGGUGAUUAGAUAUUUUACACCAGGAUUUUGAGCUUUUUGUAAGAUUUUACUGUAAAAUUAUUUCCUUUGGUUACUUUAAUAUGUACUUCAAAUAUAUCUCAUUUUGUGCUGGACGUAGUGGCUCACGCCCAUAAUCCCAGCACUUUGAGAGGCCAAGGCAGGCAGAUCACCUGAGGCCAGGAGUUCAAGACCAGCCUGGCCAACAUGGUGAAACCCCAUCUCUACUAAAAAUACAAAAAUUAGCCAGGUGUGGUGGUGCAUGUCUGUAGUCCCAGCUAUUCGGGAGGUUGAGGCAGGAGAAUCGCUUGAACGUGGGAGGCGGAGGCUGCAGUGAGCCGAGAUCGCGCCGCUACACUCCAGCCUAGGUGACGGAGCAGACUCUGUCUCAAAAAAAAAAAAAAAAAAAAAACCUCUCUGUAUAUCUCUAUCUAGCUAUCUAUGUCAUUUUGUUUGUGUGAUAGCUUUUCAGGACCAUGGUGACUGGAUAAAUCAGGUUCUGCGCUCCGUCUCCCCAUUUCCAGGUGGCUUCUGCCUGUUCAGUCCUGACACUGUUAUAAUGCCAUUUUAUCGUUUAGACAUUUGUAUGUAAACAAAUCUUGACCACUGGAAUAGUGGAAGGGGGUUCUCUUCUGGGGAGAAGGAGGAGGCAUUCAACCUGUCAGCAAGCAAAGGAGCUGGGCAGGGCCUGGAAAGCAGGAGACCAGGUUUUGGGAGACCCAGGGCACAGGGUAGCCAGAGCAGGGACCCCCAGGCCUGAGUGCUCCUCCAGUCCCUUAUGUGAGCAGGGCUCACAAGGCCUGCCCUCCCACUGCCUCUCAUACUCCAUGGGGACAAAAAGACAUAUCUAGGGGUGCUUGUUUGCAAUUUCUGAAUUUGAAGACUGAGUAACGAAUGUCAGAGUCCUGCGUUAUGCCCUCUUGGGGUCUUGCUGCCCAAAGUGAGAUCAGAGGAGCACUUUGGGGGCUUGUUGGAAAUGCAGAAUCUUACCCUCCCAUACUGGCUGUAUCUGACAAGGUUUUCAGUGAUUCCCGUGCACUUGUGGAGAAUCACAGGUCUAAUGUGUACCAACGGGGAAAAAGAAGGGAAAUUUACAGGGGCAGGAGCGCAGGAUGCUCUCCUGGGACUGCAGAGAAGUUCUGAGGACCUGGCUUUGCGGUCCUCUCAUGGAUUCAUGGGUUUGUUCUCUGGGCUCAAAAUUAUAUCCCAGGAUUGGGAGAGCAAUUUUACAGUAGGGACUUCUGCUUCUGGAUCAUCCUUGGGUCAGAAAAGCACACAUGUCUGGGUACGGUGGCCCACACCUGUAAUCCCAGUACUCUGGGAGGCUGAGGCAGGAAGAUUGCUUGAGCUCAGGAAGUCAAGACCAGGCUGGGCAACAUUGCGAGACCCUGUCUCUAUGAAAACAAAAAAUUAGCUGAGCGUAGUGUUGCAUGCCUUUAGCCCCAGCUACUCAGGAGACUGAGGUGGGGGGAUCACUGUAGCCCAGGAGUUCAAGGCUGCAGUCAGCCAUGAUCGCACCACUGCACACCAGCUUGGGCAACAAGAGACACUGUCUCUUAAAAACAAACGAACAAACAAAACAAAAAAACCUCAUAAAACAUAUAACCCAAAGAUAUUAAGGUCAAAUGUAGUGGCUCACGCCUGUAAUCCUAACACUUUGAGAGGCUAAGGCAGGAGGAUCUCUUGAGCCCAGGAGUUCAAGACCAGCCUGGGCAACAUAGUAGUCAUCUCUACUAAAAAUAAAAAUAAAAUUAGCUGGGCGUGGUGAUUGCAUACCUGUAGUCCCAUCUACUCAAGAGGCUGAGGUGGGAGGAUCGCUUGAGCCCAGGAGGUCAAGGCUGCAGUGAGUUGUGAUCAUGCCACUGCACUCCAGCCUGGGCAACAAAGCAAGACCCCAUCUCAAAAAAAAAAAAAAAAAAGAUAAUAAGCAAUAGAAUCUAUCCAUAACUUCCUCAGUUGAAUUGCUGUAGCACCUGUUUCAAUAUUUCCACCUAGAAUGAAAUGGGAAGUGCUGGUGAGAAAGGGAAGUACUGCUGGAGCCUUGGGCUCAGCCAGAGCUCUGAGGAGACCCCCCACCUCGUGGCCCCUUUGAUUUUCUCAGCCUUUGGGCUCUCCAGAGCCCGUCUCUCCCUGCCCUGGCUCCAGCAUGCCACACAUUUUCCCUACCCUGGAGGAUUGUGCUAAAGGUCAUUGUGCUAAAGGUCUACUCGCCCGUCCGUCUGUCUAUUCAUAUAUAUUGCAAAGCCUGGGAAUGAUUUCAUGUAUUUUUUCUCCAGUUGCUUUGUCUCCCUGCUUUAUCUUUUCCCUGCUUUUAGUGUCCCAUGGGUACAACUGUGUUGACUUUUAAGAACAGUUGCUUAAGGCAGCCCAGUGUGUGUGUUAGUAACAGUGUUCGUUCAGAGCCAUCCUGGGUCGGGAGCCUGCAGGCUUCCAGACUUACGCCAGGCACUUCCUGCCCAUCCUGCUGGCACUGUCUGAGAGUCCAGCCUGUAGGGACUGUCUCCGUCUUAGAAGGGAGGUAUCUGACCCUCUGCUCAGGGCCCACUGCAGGUCAGUGCCCGUGUGGUCACAGGGUCCCAUCCCUUCCCUGGCUCUGGCUUGGCCUCAGCUCAGAUGCCUCACGCCGGGACUUCCCGUUCUCUGCUGGGCUUUGUGUGCAGGGCAUUCCCCGGGCCAGUGCAAAGGCCACUAAUGCCAGAAGGGUCAGACCACCUCCCUCGUGAUGAACCAGCAGAACAUGUGGCCGGGUUGCUCCUUAAUCUGUCGCCCGCCACGAUGACUAUCAUGGUGGAGGACAUCAUGAAGCUGCUGUGCUCCCUUUCUGGGGAGAGGAAGAUGAAGGCGGCUGUCAAGCACUCUGGGAAGGGUGCCCUGGUCACAGGGGCCAUGGCCUUCGUCGGGGGUUUGGUGGGCGGCCCACCGGGACUCGCCGUUGGGGGGGCUGUCGGGGGGCUGUUAGGUGCCUGGAUGACAAGUGGACAGUUUAAGCCGGUUCCUCAGAUCCUAAUGGAGCUGCCCCCUGCCGAGCAACAGAGGCUCUUUAACGAAGCCGCAGCCAUCAUCAGGCACCUGGAGUGGACGGACGCCGUGCAGCUGACCGCGCUGGUCAUGGGCAGCGAGGCCCUGCAGCAGCAGCUGCUGGCCAUGCUGGUGAACUACGUCACCAAGGAGCUGCGGGCCGAGAUCCAGUAUGAUGACUAGGCCGCACCUCCGGGGAGGUGGGGGGCCCCUUUAAAUGACUCUGUGAUUCUGAAGAGGUGGCUUGGGAGUUGGGAGAAGCCCAGCGGAUGCCCCCUGGGGAAUCUCCACAUCAUCAGUGUAUUACUAGUAAUGUCCCGCUGGAGAGGCCACCGCUGUGCAGUGUCAUGUUCCAGAAAUUACUGAUGAAGCAGCAUGUGUUGGUGGCAUGUGCACUGGCCUGCCAUGACAGCCCUCUGACUGGCCCCCCAGUGAAGAGUAAAGGCCUGCCUGCCGCAGGCUUCGGAGGCGUCUGCUGAGUCCUCUCACCCGCAUGGGUCUGGGGAAGUGAUCACGCUCAGCCGACGGUCUGACCACACUUCAUCCUCCCCCCGGGGCCUUCUCAUCUUGGGAGAUGACUCCUCUUCAGAGCACCUGCUGCAGGACUGGAUCCCACCCCCCUGCAGGUCCUGGGGUCUCAGGGCCUUGGAGCAGCCCAUGCUGGAAUCAUGUUUACCUCCUAGUGCAACCGUCCCCUACCCAGGGACUGUCGAAUGGCCCCACGGAGGGGACGGGCGGCCUGCUGAGUGAAGCCACAAAUACCGAGUGGACUUGACCCCGGCCCCCACUAGGCUGCACACCUAGACUCGCCCUGCCAGGGCCUCGCUCUUCCCAUCUGAAAAGUCCUGGUAGUUCUUGAGGUUUACUUCUCAAAUGAAAUAUUUUUAGUAAAAAGUACAGGUAUAUCUCGGAGAUAUUGUGGGUUCAGUUCCAGACCACCUCGGUAAAGCCAACAUCACAAUAAAGCAAGGAAGCGCAUUGUUUUAGUUUCCCAGUGCAUCUAAGUCAUGUUUACUGCAUAUUGCAGUCCACUAAAUGUGCAAUAGCAUUAUGUCUAACAAAUGUACAAACCUUAAUUUAAAAAUAUUUACUGUUCAAAAUGCUGACACAGAAACGCAAAGUGAGCACAUGCUGUUGGAAAAUGGUGCCAAAUAGACUUGCCUGAUGCCAGGCUGCUACAAACCUUCAAUUUAAAAAAAAAACACAGUAUUCACAAAGCAUAGUAGAAUGAGGUAUGCCUGUAUUGCUCUUUCUGAAGUGGUGUGAUAUAAACCAUCUCUAAGAAAUGUUUCUACCCUAAAGAUUUCCCCAGUACAGUCAGCUCUCCGUAACUGUGGUCUCCACAUUUAGAUCCAACCAGCCUUGGAUAGGAAAUAUUUGAAAAAAGAAAUUGCAUUGGUACUGAACACGUACAGACCUUUUUUUCUUGCCAUUAUUCCCUAAACAAUAUGGUGUAGCAUAUUUACAUAGCAUUUAUAUUGUAUUUGGUAUUAUAAGAAAUCUAGAGAUGAUUUAAAUUAUACAGGAAGGUGUGCGUAGGUUACGUGCAAACGCUAUGCCAUUGCCCAUCAGGGACUUGAGCAUCCUCAGAUGUCGGUGUCUGAGGGUUGAGGUUGCAGUCCUGGAACCCAUCCCCCAUGGAUACUGAGGCAUAGCUGUACUGUGUGUUUUCACUUUGCUUUCAGAACUACGACUUGAAUGUGAUCGAUUACAAUAAAUGUUUUUCUAAAAAGCCAUUUUCCCACAUAUUAUGUGUAAAAUAUCUCUAAUAUUCAAAGUCUUACAAAUGGAACAAGAGGGAAGGUACCAGAUUUGUGGCUUUAAAGAAUGCAAGAGUAGGUCAGGUGAGGUGGCUCAUGCUUGUAAUGUCGGCACUUUUGGAGGCCAAAGUGGGAGGAUCGCUUGAGGCCAAGAGUUUGAAACUAGCCUGGGCAAUAUAGUGAGACCUCCAUCUCUACAAAAAAUGUUAUUCCUUGGUCCCCAGGUCCUGGGGCAGGGCAGGGACUUGGGGCUCUCCUCUCAGGCCCUGGAGGCUCGGAGGGAGGCACUUCUGCUGAGGCCCUGCUUAUAGGAAAGCUCAGUAUCCUGGCACCUCCAUGUGUGUAAGGACGUCAGGGUGAAUUAUAACCCAUGGUGAUUAAGGAAGGGCCGAGCCUUUCUCUUGCAGAGCGAUUGCUCUUCUGCUGGCCUCGUCUAGCACAAAUCAGGUGCCCUAGCACAGGCCACACUCCUGGAGUUAAUGAAGCCACUUUAAUCAUUUAUAUGCCACUUAAGUUGAUGGGGGACAGGGCAGGGGUGGGAAGGAGGGGUUGUCUGUCUGUGAAAACUGAGUGUGGCUUUUCUUGUUGAACUGAUCAUUCCUGCUCUUCCUGCAAAUAAGUCCUGCAUACGGACCCUGGAACUAAAAAUGGAAAAUCAGAGCAUGCCCCCUCCCAAUUUUGUAUAGCUUUAGUGGGCUCUAAAGUUGCCCGUUUUUAGUGUGAAGGAAAAAACGUUGAUUUGCAGAUAUCGUGAGAAUGAAACCUCAACAAAGAUGUUUGGUUCAGUGCUUCAAAGUUGGGGGACACUUUUUCCAUGUUGAACAAAUGCCAACUUCUCCGGUUGCUUACAGCAAAUCCUUCUGGAACAAUCGGGGCUGAAAUUGAGUUGCCUUUGUUAGGCGAUUGGGCCCCAUUCAUUCUUACUCGUGCAUCAGGUCCUGGUCUGUGUCAGGCCCAGGGGACACAGGUGGUCCCAGCUCAGAGGCCCAGUGUCCACUGCAGCCCCUCCCACAGCCUGCCCACCCCUACUGCAGGGAAAAAUGCCCAGGGAGGAGAUGGUCCAACUCCUGAUCAGUUUUGUGUCCGAUGGAGCAGGCCUUGCUGAGUGAAGACACUGGAACUAGCUGGGUCCUGGGGUGACUUGGAGGCUUUGGGCCUAAAAGGGCAGCCUGAACCUGGAGUCUUAUCUCCCCCAGGAGCCGAAAGCACUUUUCUUGAUUUCCCCCAGGAAAUCAAGCGCUGCUUCUCAGCUCCUGUGGUUUUAGUAUUUAUAUAUCUGUAUCUUCUUUGUAGAAAUUUAUUUAUUUUUGAAUAAGUAAUACCUGCCUGGUACAAAAUUUAAAAGGUACGGGAGGGCGCAAGCUGCAAGGGAAGGCCUGCUCCUAUGCCGACCCCAGAGGCAGCCACUGUUACCAAUUUCAUGUGUAUUCCUUUAACUCUGUUUUAAAGUAAGUCUCUGAAAACUGUUCAUUUCCUUUUGUCAGUAUUUGUUGCUGAAAACCUAGAAAAACCCAGAAAAUAUAAUGAAAUAAAAACUACAAAUUUCACAACCCAGAAAACUGCUGGUAACAGAUUUGGUGUCUUUCCUGCAAUUGUUUUAAUGCUAUGUAGGUACACAUAUAUUUUUUUCUUUUUUUCUUUUUUUUUUUUUUGAGAUGGAGUCUCGCACUGUCGCCCGGGCUGGAGUGCAGUAGCGCGAUCUUGGUUCACUGCAAGCUCUGCCUCCUGGGUUCAAGCCAUUCUCCUGCCUCAGCCUCCCGAGUAGCUUUGACUACAGUCGCCCGCCACCAUGCCCGGCUAAUUUUUAUUUUUUUAUUUUUUUUUUAUUUUUAGUAGAGACGGGGUUUCACCAUGUUAGCCAGGAUGGUCUCAAUCUCCUUACCUCGUGAUCUGCCCACCUCAGCCUCCCAAAGUGCUGGGAUUACAGGCGUGAGCCACUGCGCCCGGCCUAUGUAUGUAUAUUUCUAACGUACUUGCCUUCUUAUCCUAUAUGCCCCUUUGAACACCUGUAUCAAUGAAUGUUAAAUAAUAUUUUUGAUGUAAUUUAAAAUUCCUUGUAAAUAUUUGUAAUGGCUGCAUAAUAUUCCACUGUGCCUAACCAUGUGCCUGGUGUGAAUUCCAUUUGUGGAUUUUUACUACUGUAAUGCUGAAGUAUUACAGUAAUACUGUGUUAAUAUUCUCUUUAUUGAAUUCUGGUAUAUAGUCUUUGGGAUUCAUUCCUCAAAGUGAAAUUGCUGGAUUUAAAAGUA